ACACCUGGGGCCCAGAGCCACCGCUCAGCACGCGGGCACGCGGCGGGAGGGAAGGAAACCGCGGCGCUGGGGAUGGAGAGGGGGAAAGUGAAGAAGAAAGAGAAGGAAAAGGAGACGCAGGAGGAGAAAAUCGGAGAAAAGGGUAGGGAAGAGAAAGUGAAAAGAAAGGAGGUGGAGCAGAAAAUUAAACAAAAGCAAGAGAAGCAGGAGAGGAGAAAGGGAAAAGAGAAAGAGGAAAAGAGGACAAAGCAAGGGAAGGAGACAAACAAAGAGAAGGAACAAUUUAAGGGACAAGAAGAGAAAGGGGAGAACAAGGACAGCACCUUGACAAGGACCCCGCUCGAGCCGCUGGAGAAAAACAAGCAAAUCCUAGUGCUGGGCCUGGAUGGAGCAGGAAAAACCAGUGUCCUGCACUCUCUAGCUUCAAACAGAGUCCAGCACAGUGUGGCACCCACCCAAGGUUUCCAUGCAGUUUGCAUCAACACUGAAGACAGCCAGAUGGAGUUCCUGGAGAUUGGUGGCAGUAAACCUUUUCGGUCCUACUGGGAAAUGUACCUAUCCAAGGGAUUGCUGCUGAUCUUUGUGGUGGAUUCAGCAGAUCACAGCCGAUUACCUGAAGCCAAGAAAUACCUUCAUCAGCUAAUUGCAGCAAACCCAGUACUUCCUCUGGUUGUGUUUGCAAACAAACAGGAUCUUGAAGCAGCCUAUCACAUUACAGAUAUCCAUGAAGCUUUGGCAUUAUCUGAAGUGGGAAAUGACAGGAAGAUGUUCUUGUUUGGAACCUACCUGACUAAGAAUGGCUCAGAGAUACCCUCCACCAUGCAAGAUGCCAAAGACUUGAUUGCACAGCUGGCUGCAGAUGUGCAGUGACCAGGACUCAGCCCACUGUGCGGCUCACGACUGAGAUGUCAUCAGUGUUGAAUGGCAGGCUUGAAGCCAAAGGUUUCCACCUCAAAUAAAAAUUAAGCCAUUUCCUAUUUUCUCAGUGCAUGGGAUGUAUAUAGUUAGCCCUCCAUAUCCAUGGGUUCCACAUCUGGGGAUUCAAGAACUGUGGAUCCAAAACAUUCAAAAAGUAAACCCACUGAAGAAUAAUAACACAACAAUAAAAAUAAUACACAUUUUAAAAUACAAUAUAACAACUAUUUACAUAGCAUUUUCAUUGUAUUAGGUAUUAUAAGUAAUCUAAAGAUGAUUUAAAAUACACGAGUAGAAGUGUGUAGGUUAUAUGUAAAUAUGCCAUUUUCCAUCAGGAGCUUGAGCAUCCACAUUUGCCUGUGAGGAUCUUGGAAUCAGUCUCCCUGAGAAUACCAACGGACAACUGUACAAAGAUAAUGCUAACAUAAUAACAGCAUCUCUAUUUGGAUUUUGAAUGUUAAAAAUAUUUGUAAAACAGUGUAUUGGGGGUAUUGGGAUUUUUAAUCAACAAAGGUAAAAUGAACAUUAGCAA